GGGACUCGAACGGAAGUUCCGGCGGGGGCGGCCGAGGGGGAAGAGUGUGUCUGCGGGAGAAAGAGGAGAAUCGCCCAAGCGGCCUCGGAAGUCCCAGGGAGUGGAGGACAGAACCUGGGUGCUGUGUGGGGCUGAUGGCCUGGUGGCCUCUUGGGCCAGGAGUGUGUCCUGUGCCUGGUUUUGCUCUUGACCGCCGCCCCGAUGUAUGCAGGCCCCCGCCGUGGAGCCGUGUGGUGUAUGUGUGGUAACACCAUGUCUGUGCCCCUGCUCACCGAUGCUGCCACCGUGUCUGGAGCUGAGCGGGAAACGGCCGCGGUUAUUUUUUUACAUGGACUUGGAGACACAGGGCACAGCUGGGCUGACGCCCUCUCCACCAUCCGGCUCCCUCACGUCAAGUACAUCUGUCCCCAUGCGCCUAGGAUCCCUGUGACCCUCAACAUGAAGAUGGUGAUGCCCUCCUGGUUUGACCUGAUGGGGCUGAGUCCAGAUGCCCCAGAGGACGAGGCUGGCAUCAAGAAGGCAGCAGAGAACAUCAAGGCCUUGAUUGAGCAUGAAAUGAAGAACGGGAUCCCUGCCAAUCGAAUCGUCCUGGGAGGCUUUUCACAGGGCGGGGCCCUGUCCCUCUACACGGCCCUCACCUGCCCCCACCCUCUGGCUGGCAUCGUGGCGUUGAGCUGCUGGCUGCCUCUGCACCGGGCCUUCCCCCAGGCAGCUAAUGGCAGUGCCAAGGACCUGGCCAUACUCCAGUGCCAUGGGGAGCUGGACCCCAUGGUGCCCGUACGGUUUGGGGCCCUGACGGCUGAGAAGCUCCGGUCUGUUGUCACACCUGCCAGGGUCCAGUUCAAGACAUACCCGGGUGUCAUGCACAGCUCCUGUCCUCAGGAGAUGGCAGCUGUGAAGGAAUUUCUUGAGAAGCUGCUGCCUCCUGUCUAACUAGUCGCUGGCCCCAGUGCAGUACCCCAGCUCAUGGGGGACUCAGCAAGCAAGCGUGGCACCAUCUUGGAUCUGAGCCGGUCGAGCCCCUGUCCCCACCCUUCCUGACCUGUCCUUUUCCCACAGGCCUCUGGGGGCAGGUGGCAAGGCCUGGCCGGGCCUUCCUUCCUGGCCUUAGCCACCUGGCUCUGUCUGCAGCAGGGGCAGGCUGCUUUCUUAUCCAUUUCCCUGGAGGCGGGCCCCCCUGGCAGCAGUAUUGGAGGGGCUACAGGCAGCUGGAGAAAGGGGCCCAGCCGCUGACCCACUCACUCAGGACCUCACUCACUAGCCCCGCUUUGGGCCCCCUCCUGUGACCUCAGGGUUUGGCCCAUGGGGCCCCCCCAGGCCCCUGCCCCAACUGAUUCUGCCCAGAUAAUCGUGUCUCCUGCCUCCACUCAGCUGCUUCUCAGUCAUGAAUGUGGCCAUGGCCCCGGGGUCCCCUUGCUGCUGUGGGCUCCCUGUCCCUGGGCAGGAGUGCUGGUGAGGAGGUGGAGCCUUUUGAGGGGGGCCUUCCCUCAGCUGUUUCCCCACACUGGGGGGCUGGGCCCUGCCUCCCCGUUACCCUCCUUCCCUGCAGGCCUGGAGCCUGUAGGGCUGGACUGAGGUUCAGGUCUCCCCCCAGCUGUCUCACCCCCACUUUGUCCCCACUCUAGAGCAGGGAGGCAGUGGGGGAGGAGUUGUGUCUCGUCUUCUGUCUCCAUGUGGUUUUUGGGUGUUUUUCUUGUUGUGUCCUGGAUUCCGAUAAAAUUAAAGAAAUUGCUUCCUCAA